GCGUCCCGGGUGCCUGGAUACCGAGCGCGUCCGUAGUGGCGGCUGGCGCUAGGGAACUGCAGGGUCUAGGGUGUUGUCGGAGUGGCAGUUGGUCCGAAUUUCUCCCGAAGCCCGCGGAGGAGCGGGUAAGAGCCCCGCGAAUCCGGCCCCAACCUCGGGAACGGGAUGGGAGGCGGCCCUGGCCGCAAGCCCCGCGCUGCUAGCGGGUCCACCGCGUCGUAGCCGACAGCCGCCCUUCUUCCUCGCAGCGCGCCGCGAUUCACCAGCCUGGUCCCUUCUGCGGAGAGCGAUGCCGCUUCCCGACACCAUGUUCUGCGCUCAGCAGAUCCACAUUCCCCCGGAGCUGCCGGACAUCCUGAAGCAAUUCACCAAGGCUGCCAUCCGCACCCAGCCGGCCGACGUGCUGCGGUGGUCCGCGGGCUAUUUUUCAGCUCUGUCGAGAGGAGAUCCACUUCCUGUAAAGGACAGAAUGGAAAUGCCCACGGCAACCCAGAAAACAGACACAGGCCUGACUCAAGGACUCCUGAAAGUUUUGCACAAGCAGUGUCACCACAAGCGGUAUGUGGAAUUAACAGAUCUUGAGCAGAAGUGGAAGAACUUGUGCCUGCCGAAGGAAAAAUUCAAAGCGCUCUUACAACUGGAUCCUUGUGAAAACAAAAUCAAGUGGAUAAACUUUUUAGCGCUUGGAUGCAGCAUGCUUGGUGGGUCCUUGAACACUGCGCUGAAGCACCUGUGCGAGAUCCUCACGGACGAUCCGGAGGGCGGGCCCGCUCGCAUCCCCUUCAAGACGUUUUCCUACGUUUACCGCUACUUGGCCAGAUUAGACUCAGAUGUGUCUCCCUUGGAGACGGAAUCCUACCUUGCCUCUCUAAAGGAAAAUAUGGUCUUGUCCUGGCUGAGCACAACCAGAAUCUGGAGAGAAGAAAGCCUCAUGAUACACAGGUCAGCUAUGCUGGGCUCAGAGCAUGGAAGAGCCAGGAGAGGCUAAAGGAAUGUGCUAGACAAAGAAGUUUGAAAUAUCCAGCACACGGCCAUUCGAUGAAGACAUGGUGGGGUCCAGCACACGGCCAUUCGACCAUUUGGGUGAAGAUGCGGUGGGGGAGACUCAUACCUCCACAUAUUCAUAUGCAUGCUCACAGUGCAUACGUUGUUUCUGGAAUGAUACACAGAAAAAACUGGUAGAAACCUCCAAGGAGGAGAAGUUGGGAGGAAGGCUGCCUGUGUCUCAUUGUAUAACUUUUUUCUACCAUUUGAUUUUCACUUGUGCAUUUAUUAUGUAUUAAGUCCACCCAUCAACCGUGCAUUUAUUAUGUAUUAAGUCCACCCAUCAACCAUGCAUUUAUUAUGUAUUAAGUCCACCCAUCAACCAAUCAUGAAAAAGAAUUGGUGUCUGAGUUCUUUGGGCUUGGAGUGUAGCCAACAGGGAAUGCUUGUGAUCUAGGCUGGGCCCAUCACAGUGCUCCCCUCCUGGCCAAAGUGAUUUGCCCAAGAGAGUUGGCACAUGACCUGCACUUGACGGAUGAGAGCCUUCUCUGGGUUUUUCGGCUUGGUGCUGGGAGAGAGAGGCCCUUUUCUUCUUCCUUUGAUUAAAAAGCUUAUUAGGAUAUGGGUCUAGAGUUGUAGGUGCUAGUAGUCACUAACAUACGUGACACUGUUAUGUUGAAACAUGUUAGCUACUGAUAAUCUCAAAUUUUCAUCCCCCAAACAGCAAUUUCAUCUAGCUCAACCCCAUACGUGCCAGGCCUCAAGGAGAGUGGAUUAUACAGGGCGUGUUCACCAGGAGGGUGGGGAUUUGGGGGCCAUCUUAGAAUUCAGCCUGUUUUCCACACGCUAACUCAUUUACUCUUCAUAACCAUGUUAUCAAGUGGAAAUUAUUGUUAUUAACCUCAUAGCCAUUAUAGAUAGGUGAAGAGAAAGAGAGAUUAAUUAAGUUCCUAGUCCAACACCACACAGUGGUCCUGCUUGCCCUGCUCUCCCAGUCUGCUGUGAGCCCAGCAUGGAGCCUGUCUACACUAACGGGGUGAGGAGGAGAGGAAGGCAGAGUGCCAGGGUUCCCAGGGGCUAGGAUCAUGGUUCUUCUCCUCUCUAAGGCCAGCACCACCUCAGCUCAGCUCUCAAUUUAGUUAGACCCAGCAGGCAAGUCCCCCUCCAGGCUUACACAAUAUCAGGGUGAAUACCUGGCCUUUGCAAUUGAUUUGACCUGACUUUGAAAUCAGCCUUUUCCCUGGUUGUAGUCAGUUGAAUAGUGAGUGACUCCCAGAAAGAUAUGUCCAUGUCUCAACUCUGGAACUUACAAAUGUGGCCUUGUUUGGAAAAAGGGUCUUUGUAGAUGUCGUUAAUUUAAGGAUCACAAGAUGUGAGCAUCCUGGAUUUAGGGUGGACCCUAAAUCCAAUAACUGGUGCCCUUAAAAGAGAAAGGCAGAGGGGAGUUUGAGACACCAAUGCAGGGGAGAACACCAUGUGAAGACAGAGACAGAGAUUGGAGGAAUGCUGCCAUCACUAAGGAGUGCUUGGAGCCACCAGAAGUUGGAGGAAGCAAGGAAGGAUUCCCUCCUAAAAGCUUCAGAGGGAGCAGGGUCCUGCCGAUACCUUGAUUUUGGACUUACGGUCCCCAGAACUGUGAGACAAGAAAUUGUUGCUGUUUGAAGCCACCAAGUUUGUGGUAAUGUGUUUCAACAACCCUAGGAAAUGAGCACACUUAUUACCUCUUUUCUUGCAAACCAAGUCCAAAGGGGACACCAGAAAUGGGACAGAGCCCUGAAGCAAGACCUGGGUUUGGUUUUCUUUUGAUUCCGAAAAUAACAGCCCUUUAAGGAAUCAAGAGGUUGGGGAGAGGUUGAGGCUGAAGAAAGUUGAAGAACUGAAAGAAUCUUGGCUCAUUUGGAGGAUAAGAGAGAGUUCUAGAAUGGAGAGAAGAUAGACCUGCUCUAGAAAAAUUUUCUGGCUGGGCGCAAUGGUUCAUGCCUGUAAUCCCAACACUUUAGGAGGCUGAGGCAGGUGGAUCUCCUGAGUGCAGGAGUUCGAGACCACCCUGGGUUACAUGGCAAAUCCCCGUCUCUACUAAAAUACAAAAAAUUAGCUGGGCGUGGUGGCGCACACCUGUGGUCCCAGCUACUCAGGAGGCUGAGGCACAAAAAUCGCUUGAGCCCCGGAGGUGGAGGUUGCAAUGAGCUGAGAUUGCACCACUGCACUCCAGCUUGGGCUACAGAGUGAGACUGUGUCUC